GGUGUUGCGCUUCUCGCCGGGGAAGGGACGGCUUUGGGGACGUCGGAGAGCGGGCAUUCUGGAAAGCGUGGGGUGAGUCAGCCCUGCACACUGGAGAACUAGUUUUCAGAAGGAAAAACAGGACGCGGGGUUCCCCAGCCCCGCACCUCGUUUCUCAGGCUGUGCGCCGCGGUGACUGCCAGCGCAGGCUCCCUUCCCUAGGCCGUCCCGCGUUGCAAAACCUGCAGACGGGCACCUUGCAGAAGACGCAGUGUUCGGGAAUCAGAACCACAGCCGCCCAUCACCUCUUCAUGACCACUGCCUGCCAGGAGGCUAACUACGGUGCCCUCCUCCGGGAGCUCUGCCUCACCCAGUUCCAGGUAGACAUGGAGGCCGUCGGGGAGACGCUGUGGUGUGACUGGGGCAGGACCAUCAGGAGCUACAGGGAGCUGGCCGACUGCACCUGGCACAUGGCGGAGAAGCUGGGCUGCUUCUGGCCCAAUGCAGAGGUGGACAGGUUCUUCCUGGCAGUGCAUGGCCGCUACUUCAGGAGCUGCCCCAUCUCAGGCAGGGCCGUGCGGGACCCGCCCGGCAGCAUCCUCUACCCCUUCAUCGUGGUCCCCAUCACGGUGACCCUGCUGGUGACGGCACUGGUGGUCUGGCAGAGCAAGCGCACUGAGGGCAUUGUGUAGGCGGGGCCCAGGCUGCCCGCGGGUGCACCCAGGCUGCAGGGUGAGGCCAGGCAGGCCUGGGUAGGGGCAGCUUCUGGAGCCUUGGGACAGAGCAGGCCCACAAUGCCCCCCUUCUUCCAGCCAAGAAGAGCUCACAGGAGUCCAGAGUAGCCGAGGCUCUGGUAUUAACCUGGAAGCCCCCCUGGCUGGAGGCCACCGCCACCCUAGGAAGGGGGCAGGGACGUGACCUUGACUUACCUCUGGAAAGGGUCCCAGCCUAGACUGCUUACCCCAUAGCCACAUUUGUGGAUGAGUGGUUUGUGAUUAAAAGGGAUGUUCUUGAA